ACACACGCGCACACUCACACGGGCGCGCGCAGCCCCUCCGGCCGCGGGCGCAGCGGGGGCGCUGGUGGAGCUGCGAAGGGCCAGGUCCGGCGGGCGGGGCGGCGGCUGGCACUGGCUCCGGACUCUGCCCGGCCAGGGCGGCGGCUCCAGCCGGGAGGGCGACGUGGAGCGGCCACGUGGAGCGGCCCGGGGGAGGCUGGCGGCGGGAGGCGAGGCGCGGGCGGCGCAGCAGCCAGGAGCGCCCACGGAGCUGGACCCCCAGAGCCGCGCGGCGCCGCAGCAGGUGGGUGACACCCCGCCCCGGCCGGCCGGAGACCCGAGCCCAUCGCCGUCAGCCAGCCAGGGCCGCGCGGGUUCCAGGAAGGAUGUUACCUUUGACGAUGACAGUGUUAAUCCUGCUGCUGCUCCCCACGGGUCAGGCUGCCCCAAAGGAUGGAGUCACAAGGCCAGACUCUGAAGUGCAGCAUCAGCUCCUGCCCAACCCCUUCCAGCCAGGCCAGGAGCAGCUCGGACUUCUGCAGAGCUACCUAAAGGGACUAGGAAGGACAGAAGUGCAACUGGAGCAUCUGAGCCGGGAGCAGGUUCUCCUCUACCUCUUUGCCCUCCAUGACUAUGACCAGAGUGGACAGCUGGAUGGCCUGGAGCUGCUGUCCAUGUUGACAGCUGCUCUGGCCCCUGGAGCUGCCAACUCUCCUACCACCAACCCGGUGAUCUUGAUAGUGGACAAAGUGCUCGAGACCCAGGACCUGAAUGGGGAUGGGCUCAUGACCCCUGCUGAGCUCAUCAACUUCCCGGGAGUAGCCCUCAGGCACGUGGAGCCCGGAGAGCCCCUUGCUCCAUCUCCUCAGGAGCCACAAGCUGUUGGAAGGCAGUCCCUAUUAGCUAAAAGCCCAUUAAGACAAGAAACACAGGAAGCCCCUGGUCCCAGAGAAGAAGCAAAGGGCCAGGUAGAGGCCAGAAGGGAGUCUUUGGAUCCUGUCCAGGAGCCUGGGGGCCAGGCAGAGGCUGAUGGAGAUGUUCCAGGGCCCAGAGGGGAAGCUGAGGGCCAGGCAGAGGCUAAAGGAGAUGCCCCUGGGCCCAGAGGGGAAGCUGGGGGCCAGGCAGAGGCUGAAGGAGAUGCCCCCGGGCCCAGAGGGGAAGCUGGGGGCCAGGCAGAGGCUGAAGGAGAUGCCCCCGGGCCCAGAGGGGAAGCUGGGGGCCAGGCAGAGGCCAGGGAGAAUGGAGAGGAGGCCAAGGAACUUCCAGGGGAAACACUGGAGUCUAAGAACACCCAAAAUGACUUUGAGGUGCACAUUGUUCAAGUGGAGAAUGAUGAGAUCUAGAUCUUGAAGAUACAGGUACCCCACGAAGUCUCAGUGCCAGAACAUAAGCCCUGAAGUGGGCAGGGGAAAUGUACGCUGGGACAAGGACCAUCUCUGUGCCCCCUGCCUGGUCCCAGUAGGUAUCAGGUCUUUCUGUGCAGCUCAGGGAGACCCUAAGUUAAGGGGCAGAUUACCAAUAAAGAACUGAAUGAAUUCAUCCCCCCGGCCACCUCUCUACCCGUCCAGCCUGCCCAGACCCUCUCAGAGGAACGGGGUUGGGGACCGAAAGGACAGGGAUGCCGCCUGCCCAGUGUUUCUGGGCCUCACGGUGCUCCGGCAGCAGAGCGCAUGGUGCUAGCCAUGGCCGGCUGCAGAGGACCCAGUGAGGAAAGCUCAGUCUAUCCCUGGGCCCCAAACCCUCACCGGUUCCCCCUCACCUGGUGUUCAGACACCCCAUGCUCUCCUGCAGCUCAGGGCAGGUGACCCCAUCCCCAGUAAUAUUAAUCAUCACUAGAACUUUUUGAGAGCCUUGUACACAUCAGGCAUCAUGCUGGGCAUUUUAUAUAUGAUUUUAUCCUCACAAUAAUUCUGUAGCCAAGCAGAAUUGGUUCCAUUUGACAGAUGAAGAAAUUGAGGCAGAUUGCGUUAAGUGCUGUACCCUAAGGUGAUAUGCAGCUAAUUAAAUGGCAGAUUUUAAUCCA